GGCUUCCGGCGGCGUGACCUGACCGCAAGAGGCCAAUGGAGUGUGGGAGCUGAAAGGGUCUUCGCUGGCGGCCGGUAACUGGCGGCGGUUGGGAACGGCCGAGUGUGGCUCUUCUGGUGUUUCAGCUUGGGGAGAGAGGGGUGGCCUUCCUCUUGCAGUUGAGGCCGGCGCCGAGCCGGACUUCAGGCGGAUCUCGUGGCGGAGCCCAUCUUGCUCCCUCUCCCAGGCCUUUACCCGCUCCCUAGGAUUCCCGGGCCCUGUAGGUGGGAGUUGGGAGACGUGAGUUCUCUUUCAUUCUGCGCCUCUCAUUGGCUCUCUGACCUUGUGCGGAACGCGUCCUUUAGCUGACCUCAGCUGCAUUUUUUAGAAGAUGGAGAUUGUAUUCACAGUGACUGUCAGCUUUUUAACGGCGGGAACUGACGUAGUGUUAAACACUGUCGUGUAUCGCUGGCACAGCACAAGGACAUUAUAGGUAUUCUGUACUCAAUUAAGUUAUUUUGAGUCACAGACCUUUUGAAAAUCUCGUGUAAGCUAUGGCCCCUCCACCUCUCUAAUACUUCCCCCGGCCCCCACCCCAAGCACACACAAAAGCUUAUGCAUAGGAAAUUUGUUUUACUAUUUCGGAUUACUUCCAAGAUCUCUCUCCUGAUGCCCAUCUAUGGAUCCCAGAGUCUGGCAAGUAGUAGGCGUUUGAACAUUUGUAAUCAUUAGAUAGUAAGUAUUCAGUUAACCAUUUUUAUUUUUAAUUUUUUCUUUUUUUUUUUUUUUUUUUUUGAGACAGGGCCUCACUGUGUCACCCAGGCUGGAGUGCAGUCCUCCCACCUCAGCCUCCCAAGUAGCUGGACUCCAGGCGCCCACCACCACGCCCAGCUAUUUUUUGUGUUUUUGGUAGAGAUGAGAUUUUGCCAUCUUACGCAGAUUGGUCUCGAACUCUUGGCCUCAAGCAAUCUACUCACCUCAGCUCCCUAAAGUGCUGGGAUUACAGGCAUGAGCCAGUGUGCCCAGCCCAGUUAAUCAUUUUUAAAUGCAUGAAAUGCUAUUUCACAGGAGGGAAGAAGAUAGAUAGCCUAUUAAUAAGUUUUAAUUAUUGGCCUAACCAGGUACUACUCUCACUUGUCUCCUAACGACUCUAGGAAAGAGGACAGUACUGCUUUUAAAGAGACAGUGUUAGGGAUCUUGGAAGCACAGCCAACAUGUGUGACAUUGAAGAAGCCACUAACCAACUCCUAGAUGUGAACCUUCAUGAGAACCAGAAGUCUGUACAAGUGACAGAAAGUGACCUCGGAAGUGAAUCUGAGCUUCUAGUCACUAUUGGAGCCACUGUACCUACUGGCUUUGAGCAAACAGCUGCAGAUGAAGUCAGAGAGAAACUUGGGUCAUCAUGCAAAAUCAGCAGAGACCGUGGCAAGAUAUAUUUUGUCAUUUCAGUGGAAAGUCUGGCACAGGUUCAUUGUCUGAGAUCAGUUGAUAACUUAUUUGUGGUGGUUCAGGAGUUUCAAGAUUACCAGUUCAAACAAACAAAGGAAGAAGUUCUAAAGGAUUUUGAAGACUUGGCUGGAAAACUCCCAUGGUCAAACCCCUUAAAAGUGUGGAAAAUUAAUGCCAGUUUUAAAAAGAAAAAAGCAAAGCGCAAAAAGAUAAAUCAGAAUUCAAGUAAAGAGAAGAUUAAUAAUGGACAAGAAGUCAAAAUCGAUCAGAGAAAUGUUAAAAAAGAGUUCACUAGCCAUGCUUUAGAUUCUCAUAUCUUAGAUUAUUAUGAAAAUCCAGCCAUCAAAGAGGAUGUAUCAACAUUAAUAGGUGAUGAUUUGGCAUCUUGCAAAGAUGAGACUGAUGAAAGCUCAAAAGAAGAAACUGAGCCUCAAGUGCUGAAGUUUAGAGUCACAUGCAACAGGGCAGGAGAGAAACAUUGCUUUACCUCAAAUGAGGCUGCAAGAGAUUUUGGGGGUGCUGUUCAAGAUUAUUUUAAGUGGAAGGCCGACAUGACCAACUUUGAUGUGGAGGUUCUUUUGAACAUCCAUGAUAAUGAAGUCAUUGUGGGCAUUGCAUUGACUGAAGAGAGUCUCCACCGAAGAAAUAUAACACAUUUUGGACCUACAACUCUUAGAUCAACUCUUGCCUAUGGGAUGCUCAGGCUCUGUGAUCCUCUACCUUAUGAUAUAAUAGUCGAUCCAAUGUGUGGAACUGGGGCAAUACCAAUAGAGGGGGCCACUGAAUGGUCUGACUGUUUCCAUAUUGCUGGUGAUAAUAAUCCACUGGCUGUGAAUAGAGCAGCAAAUAACAUUGCAUCUUUAUUGACCAAGAGCCAAAUUAAAGAAGGCAAACCCUCCUGGGGCUUGCCCAUAGAUGCUGUUCAGUGGGAUAUCUGCAAUCUGCCAUUGAGAACUGGCUCUGUGGAUAUUAUUGUAACAGAUUUGCCAUUUGGAAAAAGGAUGGGAUCCAAGAAGAGAAACUGGAACCUUUAUCCAGCUUGCCUACGGGAGAUGAGCCGUGUCUGCACACCUACCACAGGCCGAGCUGUACUACUUACUCAAGACACAAAAUGCUUUACCAAGGCGUUAUCUGGAAUGCGACACGUAUGGCGAAAGGUGGAUACAGUCUGGGUGAACGUUGGUGGUCUUCGUGCUGCAGUUUACGUUCUGAUACGUACACCUCAAGCUUUUGUUCAUCCUUCAGAACAAGACGGAGAAAGAGGAACUCUUUGGCAAUGCAAAGAAUGAAGAUGACUAAUAGUACUUGUACUUCCCACCACUGGAAAUGUUAGCAUAAAAGAACUUGGAGAGGAAAAAAGUAUUAACAAAACUGCAGUCUGCACUCUUUAAACCUGUUUAAGGCUCUUCAUCCUGGUUAGCAAAAGGUGUGAAUGUAAUGUGAUGGAAUUUAAAAGUUUUAUGAGACCAGGCACAGUGGCUCACGACUGUAAUUCCAGCAGUUUAGGAAGCCGAAGUGUGCAGAUCACCUGAGGUCCGGAGACCAGCCUGGCCAACAUGGUGAAACCCUGUCUCUACUAGAAAUACAAAAAUUAGCCAGGUGUGGUGGCGGGCGCCUGUAAUCCCAACUACUCAGGAGGCUGAGGCUAGAGAAUCACUUGAACCCAGCAGGCGGAGGUUGCGGUGAGUCGAGAUCACGCCAUUGCACUCCAGCCUGUGCGACAAGAGCGAAACUCUGUCUCAAAAAGAUUUUAUAAGAAAGCAGAGCUUUUCCUUGAAGCUCUUUUGAAGUGGUAGCUUAAUUAGUAUUUUGUUGAAAAUACUUUAAAGAUGCCUAGUGAAAAGCCUACUAAAGUGCUGUGAGAUUGGGGUUUAGAACAUUUUAUUUUCAGGCUUUAUGGCCUAUUUUCCAUUGUGUCAAGUGCAAAACUACCCUGGCCCAAAGGAAGGGCAGAGAACAUAAUUACAUCUUAGGCCACAUUUCAUUCUUUGCAGCUUUGCUAAUCCAGUUGCUCAAGUUCUUUACCUCAACCUGAAGGAAUGAAGCAUUAUUACAUUUUGUGAAUGGUGUUCAGCCUAUAAGACGAAGUCUCACAAGACCUAUAGGAAAGUUUACCAUCUGCCUUAAAUAUUAAAAUAUCCAUCUGUUAUUCACAUUAAUACACAGAAUGAAAAUAGAGGUCUAGGAAUUAUCAAAGGUACUGCAAAAAUACUGUAUAGAACUUAUUUGUAAAUAGCACAUACAUUGAUAGAUGGGGUGUGGGACCAACAAACCAAAUUAAAAGAAAUUGUUUUUCUUUCAGUACACUAAGGUGUGUGUUUUCAAAACCAAACACAAACCUGUCAAGAGUAUUUGUUGGCUAGUUUCUUAAAAGGCCAAGAGAAAAAAAAUGAUAUAUCUUUGGAAAACUUUUAAUUUGGGAGUUAUGUGAGUUGUUACUUUCUCCUGGAUCACGAUUCACAUUUAAUUGCUUUUCCAGUUGCAACAAGUCCUUCUUGAGAGUUUUGUGGAAAAUGGUGCUUCCCUGGAACAAAGAGUAGUUGAGGUUUUUUUGUGGAACUCAUCAUAGUAUUGUUUAUUUUGGAGCCUCUGGCUGCAAUCAGUAUAGAUUUUCAGUAUCCUAUUAGUAUUAUAAUAGUACUCCUCUUAAUACUUUCUGAUGUCUCCAUUGAGAAUAAAAGGACACAAUACUUUUGAAAGAAGAGUUCACAUUAGCAGCACAGCCAGCAAUCCUCAUCUGGUUUCUCUGAUCUCCUACCCCACACUUCAUAAUGAAUGGGAAAUAAGAUGUUUAUGAAGGUUUUAUAUCCUAGACUGGCCUUUUUACCACUAUCAGAAUUCACAGCUGCUUUGUUUAUGGGCCGAACACAAAACUUUUCACCUGAUGGGAGAAACCAUUUAAACCUCAAAUUAAGCAACCCACAGAACCAGGAAGUUCAAGGACCAUGUCUGUUUUCACCACGAUGUCUUUCCCCACCCCCCCACCCCCCACUCCACCCCCCACUAAGGGCAGGGUAUUGUAUCUGCCAGACUGGGUAUUUGUUGAACAAGCGAGUAUUUUCGCCUAUUAGCUUAGUUUUUAAGGAAAUCAUUUUUUACUUGAUUCAUCAUAGCUUUAAUUCUAUUACAUACUACAAUAAAAAUUUGACAAGACUGAUACAAAUAUGUAGUGGGCAAUAGUUUGCCGUCUUCUUCCCUAGUAUGGUGUUUUUCAAUCUGGUGACUAGAAUAGGCAGUGGGCUAUAAGCAGGAUUCAUAAGGCCUGGAGCUGAGUUAUAUGUGACACUGCCACCUAUUCAUUGUGUGACCUUGGUUUUAACCUUCAAAGUGGGUCUCCUGGACUAAAAGAAUGUGAAAAGAUGGGGAAAUAAAUCUGUAAUCUGAACAUGGAA